AUUUACACAUUUCCCUCCUCAGCAAUGGGUACACAGACAGCCAAGCUCCUGGACUAAGUCUCUGAAUGUGUAUCUGACACUUCCCCUUACUGAGCUCCGGAGGCUCCUUCUUGCCGAGCUCCGGAGGCUCCCAGUGACCUCUUGAUAAUCAGCCUUGGCGGGGCCCAAAUACCACCCCUUGGAAAACUCACUGAGCCUGACAUCUGCCUGUAAGCAGCUUUCAGGAAGGAUCUCACAAACACCCACCCAAUCUCUCUUGGUAGCAAAUUGUCAAAUCAUACCCAUUUCCUCAAAAGAUGGUGGAGGACUUAGCAGCCUCCUAUAUUGUUCUGAAAUUGGAGAAUGAAAUUCGGCAGGCUCAAGUGCAGUGGCUGAUGGAAGAAAAUGCUGCUCUCCAGGCCCAGAUCCCAGAGCUUCAGAAGUCCCAAGCAGCCAAGGAGUAUGAUCUACUCCGAAAGUCCUCAGAGGCCAAGGAGCCCCAGAAGCUCCCAGAGCACAUGAAUCCCCCAGCAGCCUGGGAGGCCCAAAAGACCCCAGAGUUCAAGGAACCCCAGAAGCCACCAGAGCCACAGGAUCUUCUACCCUGGGAACCCCCAGCAGCCUGGGAACUCCAGGAGGCCCCAGCAGCCCCAGAGUCCCUGGCGCCUCCAGCAACCCGGGAGUCCCAGAAACCUCCAAUGGCCCAUGAGAUCCCAACAGUCUUGGAGGGCCAGGGGCCUGCAAACACCCAGGAUGCCACAAUAGCCCAAGAGCCCAAGAAUUCAGAACCCCAGGAUCCCCCAAAUAUUGAGAAGCCCCAGGAGGCACCAGAAUACCAGGAAACUGCAGCACAGCUAGAGUUCCUUGAGCUUCCACCUCCCCAGGAGCCUCUGGAGCCUUCAAAUGCCCAGGAAUUCCUAGAACUCUCAGCAGCCCAGGAGUCCCUGGAGGGUCUAAUAGUUGUGGAGACAUCAGCAGCUUCAGAGUUUCCACAGGCCCCUAUUGGGUUAGAGGCUACAGAUUUCCCCCUGCAAUACACUUUAACCUUCAGUGGAGAUUCCCAGAAGCUUCCUGAGUUCCUGGUUCAGCUGUAUAGUUACAUGAGAGUCAGAGGGCACCUGUAUCCCACUGAAGCAGCCCUGGUGAGCUUUGUUGGCAAUUGCUUCUCAGGUAGGGCAGGAUGGUGGUUCCAGCUCUUACUGGAUAUCCAAAGCCCCUUACUGGAGCAAUGUGAAAGUUUCAUACCUGUGCUCCAGGAUACUUUUGAUAAUCCAGAAAACAUGAAAGAUGCCAACCAGUGCAUCCAUCAACUCUGCCAAGGGGAGGGUCAUGUAGCAACCCACUUCCACCUCAUUGCUCAAGAGCUGAACUGGGAUGAAAGCACUCUCUGGAUCCAAUUUCAAGAAGGUCUUGCCAGUUCUAUACAAGAUGAACUGUCUCACACAAGCCCAGCCACCAACCUAUCUGAUCUCAUCACUCAGUGCAUCAGCCUGGAAGAGAAGCCUGAUCCCAAUCCAUUAGGGAAAAGUUCCUCUGCAGAGGGAGAUGGACCCGAGAGUCCACCAGCUGAAAACCAACCUAUGCAGGCUGCAAUCAACUGCCCACACAUCAGUGAAGCUGAAUGGGUCCGUUGGCACAAAGGCCGCUUAUGCCUCUACUGUGGUUAUCCUGGUCAUUUUGCCAGAGAUUGCCCUGUCAAGCCUCAUCAGGCCCUGCAGGCGGGAAACAUCCAGGCCUGCCAGUAAGGGGGACCCCACGUGGGCCAAUCUACAAAUAUGCGUCCCCCUCUCUUCCAAUAUCCAUGUCUCAUACACUAUGGCUUACUGUUGAAAUCCAACUGGGAAGAAGAUAAUUCUUUGAGCAAGCAAUGGUAGAUUCAGGCUCCUACAGAAACAGCAUUGAUCAUACUGUGGUUCUUCGAGAGAAGCUGCCCAUCCGCAGUAAUAUCUUCCCUCUGAUGCUGGAAACUGUCGACGGCCAUCCACUUAUUAAUGGACCCAUAACUAAGGAAACAUCACCUGUCCAAGUUCAAAUUGGAAACCAUGUUGAAGAGCUCCAGUUUGACAUUAUUCAUGCACCACGAUACCCUCUGAUUAUUGGAAUCCAUUGGCUUGAGACACAUGACCCAAACAUAGAAUGGAGUACCCGCACUGUGUCCUUUCUAUCACGUUAUUGUCACUACAAUUGCUUCAGGCACAGGUGGAAUAGAAGAAAUCGUGAUGAAAUAAUUUCUGGGUAGAUCCUGUGUCCUAGUGACUGUUCCUGGCAACCUGUCUUCUGUUACCUCAGCUGUCAUCAGCAUUUGCUGCUCCCUGAAUCUUCUACUGAACAUCUUGCUAUGUACUAAGGCUACCUGUACAACGACUCUGCCUCUUAGAUGAUAGACUGAACCUGAUGACUUUGAGCUGCUUUUUUUUUUUUCACUAACUCUGCAUGCCUCUAUCUCAGAACUCUGCAUCCUGCGGAACUGUUUUAAUUACAAUUAUACUAACAAUACACAUGAGAAUAGAUAUUAGAAACUAAUAAUGAAAAAGCAUAGCUGUUAAACUGACUUGAUUUUUUUCUUAUCAAUAUUUUCUAUAUCACAAAAAUGGCAACAUCUUUUACAUAAAGAAAAUAAGUUUGUAAGUGAUAUUUCUUAAAAGAAUCAAUAAAUAUUAGCAAUUUCUA